ACUUUCUAAUUGUAAGGAAGUGCGCUAGUAGUCCACCGAGGAUCCUCGAGGUUGGCCUUAUUGUAUCAUAAUUUAACGAAUUUGCGUUCCAGGUUGUUACAGCCUUUGAAAUAAUGGCCUCAUAUUUAAGAAUGUAGCAAUUUUUCUUUGAAAUUUCCGAAAGUGGGGAAAAAAGUAAUAGAAGACUGCACCUAUAUGGAAUUAUUUUCUGAUUCGCAGUUCUUUAUAAUCGUAGACUUAAUUUGGUGGCUUUAUUGGACCUGUUUGAAACAGGAAGCCUUUCUGUAAUGUGGUUUCGGGUCGGCUUCACCUCUGGCACUCUCUGAAACGUCGUUGUCUAUGGUUUCCCUAAGAAGCUAGAAUGAGCGGGAUGCUACGGAGGGAGGUGUAUACAGAGUCAUCUUAGUGGGAUUUGGGGAAGCAACAGGGCUGUGUGGGGUAACCUGCCACCUUUAAGUGGAAAUCAGAAAUGGAGCAAGAGCCACAAAAUGGAGAACCUGCUGAAAUUAAGAUCAUCAGAGAAGCAUAUAAGAAGGCCUUUUUAUUUGUUAACAAAGGUCUGAAUACAGAUGAAUUAGGUCAGAAGGAAGAAGCAAAGAACUACUAUAAGCAAGGAAUAGGACACCUGCUCAGAGGGAUCAGCAUUUCAUCAAAAGAGUCUGAACACACAGGUCCUGGGUGGGAAUCUGCUAGACAGAUGCAACAGAAAAUGAAAGAAACUCUACAGAAUGUACGCACCAGGCUGGAAAUUCUAGAGAAGGGUCUUGCCACUUCUCUGCAGAAUGAUCUUCAGGAGGUGCCCAAGUUAUAUCCAGAAUUUCCACCUAAAGACAUGUGUGAAAAAUUACCAGAGCCUCAGUCUUUUAGUUCAGCUCCUCAGCAUGCUGAAGUAAAUGGAAACACCUCAACUCCAAGUGCAGGGGCAGUUGCUGCACCUGCUUCUCUGUCUUUACCAUCACAAAGUUGUCCAGCAGAAGCUCCUCCUGCUUAUACUCCUCAAGCUGCUGAAGGUCACUACACUGUAUCCUAUGGAACAGAUUCUGGGGAGUUUUCAUCAGUUGGAGAGGAGUUUUAUAGGAAUCAUUCUCAGCCACCGCCUCUUGAGACCUUAGGGCUGGAUGCAGAUGAAUUGAUUUUGAUACCAAAUGGAGUACAGAUUUUUUUUGUAAAUCCUGCAGGGGAGGUUAGUGCACCUUCGUAUCCUGGGUACCUUCGAAUUGUGAGGUUUUUGGAUAAUUCUCUCGAUACGGUUCUAAACCGUCCUCCCGGGUUUCUUCAGGUUUGUGACUGGUUAUAUCCUCUAGUUCCUGAUAGAUCUCCGGUUCUGAAAUGUACUGCGGGAGCCUACAUGUUUCCUGAUACAAUGCUACAAGCAGCAGGAUGCUUUGUGGGGGUCGUCCUGUCCUCUGAGUUACCAGAGGAUGAUAGAGAGCUCUUUGAGGAUCUGUUAAGGCAAAUGUCUGACCUUCGGCUCCAGGCCAACUGGAACAGAGCAGAAGAAGAAAAUGAAUUCCAAAUCCCUGGAAGAACUAGACCCUCCUCUGACCAACUAAAAGAAGCCUCUGGCACUGAUGUGAAACAGUUGGACCAAGGCAAUAAGGAUGUACGUCAUAAAGGAAAACGUGGAAAAAGGGCUAAAGAUACUUCAAGUGAAGAAGUUAACCUGAGUCACAUUGUACCAUGUGAGCCAGUUCCAGAAGAAAAGCCAAAAGAAUUACCUGAAUGGAGUGAAAAAGUGGCUCACAACAUUUUGUCAGGUGCUUCCUGGGUGAGUUGGGGUUUAGUCAAAGGUGCUGAGAUUACUGGUAAGGCAAUCCAGAAAGGUGCUUCUAAACUCCGAGAGCGGAUUCAACCAGAAGAAAAACCCGUGGAAGUUAGUCCAGCUGUCACCAAGGGACUUUAUAUAGCGAAGCAAGCUACAGGAGGAGCAGCAAAAGUCAGUCAGUUCCUGGUUGAUGGAGUUUGCACUGUAGCAAAUUGCGUUGGAAAAGAACUAGCUCCACAUGUCAAGAAGCAUGGAAGCAAACUUGUUCCAGAAUCUCUUAAAAAAGACAAAGAUGGGAAAUCUCCUCUGGAUGGUGCUAUGGUUGUAGCAGCAAGUAGUGUUCAAGGAUUUUCAACUGUCUGGCAAGGAUUGGAAUGUGCAGCUAAAUGCAUCGUUAACAAUGUUUCAGCAGAAACUGUACAAACUGUCAGAUACAAAUACGGAUAUAAUGCAGGAGAAGCUACCCACCAUGCGGUGGAUUCUGCGGUCAAUGUUGGCGUAACUGCCUACAAUAUUAACAACAUUGGUAUCAAAGCAAUGGUGAAGAAAACUGCAACACAAACAGGACACACUCUCCUUGAGGACUAUCAGAUAGUUGAUAAUUCUCAGAGGGAAAAUCAAGAAGGAGCAGCAAAUGUCAACGUGAGAGGGGAGAAGGAUGAGCAGACGAAGGAAGUAAAGGAGGCAAAGAAGAAAGAUAAAUGAUGAAGUGCUGGGAAUCACUUAUACCAAAGCCUUAUGAAAUGGAUGAAAUUUUGUUAAAUAGGCAAAUGUGGAAUUCCUCACAGAUUAACCAGUAUUUUUUAAAUGUAUUCAUUCCUACAAAUUAACUUUCAUAAAUUUUAUGGCAUGUCUUCUAUUUAAAAGGAAAAGAAUAAGUAUUCUUGCAUCUGGCCUUAGAAAUGUGAAGUUAUAUUCUCAAGUUUAUUUUUUUCCAAGUGUAGCUAAAAUAUUUUUGCAGGUAAAAUAAAGCUGAUAGUACAUGUGUUGUUCAAACCUUGUUAAACCUAAUAUUGAACUAUUUUUAUAUCUGCUGUCUUUCAGAAGGCAAAUAGGAAACUAUAUAUUUGCUUAAAAAUUGGCAUUUAGUAACCUUAAUUCUUUUUAUAGAAGGAAUGACUUAAAGUAUUGUCCCCUCUUUUUGCACUAAUUGUGGAUUUUUUUAGAUGCUUCUCAAAAUUUUCAGUGUGUAAGCUAAACAAAAACUAAAACUAAGAAUUCUCAAAAAAACUUGUUCAAAACAGGGAAAGACUGAUGAAAAGUAAAAUGGACUACUUUUGUAACUUACCUGUUUGUUAGGAAAUGGAAUGGUCUCUUUGAUUUAAAAUAAAUAAAAAUAGAUUAUUACGUCUUUUGUAUUGAGACUGUAUUGUUAUGAGCCUAGGAAAUUUGGGAACAUGAUUGUAUUGUAUUAAAAUUCGAAGUGAUUAUUAUCAGCUUAAUUGGAUUAAAAAAGUACUUCAAGAAAUUAUUUUAUCAUAUCUGCUUCUGUUUUUCCAAAAGGUUAAAACUUGUAAAAAAAAUAUAUAUAAACAAUUGAGUUUACUAAUGGUAAACAUUUUUAUUCUGGGAUUCGGUCAUUGGAAUUUAUAUUAAAAGACAAGUUAUUAAAAAGGAAAGGUUCUAUUCAUAAUCAGGGUAAAGAAUAUGAAAACCUUAGACGUAAUCCAUGGUGGAUAGGCAUUAUGGUUUCCACUUUGGCAGAAGGCAGACUAUUCACAGCCCUAUUUACUUACAUAGGCUAAAAAACUAUGUAACUAAAUACCUAAUGGUAUUUAAUUUUUGUUUAUUGAAUUUAAGAGAUUGGUAUUAGUUUUCAUAGCUGUAGUCCAUUCUAAUAAUUUCUGAUCUUCUAGUGGCUACUUAAUUAGACAUUAUUUGAAGCUGUCUGAAGAAUGCACUUUAUGAAUUAAAAAACUGAAUUGCCUGACCUCGUUAUCACAUGAGCUUAUAUUUUGGGAACACAUAGAACUGAUGGAGGCUUUUCCUAAGGCCAAGGAUAAUGUACUAGUUGUUAAAAUGGAAAUAAAAGUGAAGUGGUAAAUAGCUUACAGACAGUCUAUGCUUUGUUUAAGAAAUGGAAUGGCACUUCAUAUAUUCUCAUUUGUGGGAGCUAAAAAUUACAAUAAUCAAACUUAAGGAGAUAGAGAGUAGAAUGAUGGUUACCAGAGGCUGGGAGGCAUUGAAGGGAUGGGGAGGGAAGUGAGGUUGAUUAAUGGGUACGAAAAUAUAGUUAGAACGAAUUUGUUGUAGUAUUUGAUAGCCCAACAGGGUGACUACAGUCAACAAUAACUUUAUACAUUUAAAAAUAAAAGAGUGUAAUUGGGACGUUUGUAACACAAAUGAAUGCUUGAAGCAGUAGAUACACCCUGAUGUAAUUAUUAUAAAUCGCAUACCUGUAUCAAAAUAUCUCAUGUAUCCCAUAAAUAUAUACACCUACCAUGUACCCAUAAAAAUUUAAAAAGAAAUGGAAUGGCAAAUAAUGGAACAUAAACUUUAAACAGUUAGCUUUGACCAGAGGUCAGCAAAUAUCCUCCAUGGGCUAAAUCCAGAUGUCCACCUGUUUUCAUAAAUAACGUUUUAUUGGAGCAUAGCUGUACCCAUUUGUUUACAUAUUGGCUAUGGCUGCUGUCUAGUUCAACGUGAGAGUUGAAUAGUUGCAUCAGAGAGUAUAUGGUCCACAAGCCUAACUUAUUCACUCUCUGGCCCUUUGCAGAAAAAGUGUGCUGCCUUAGUCUAUAGAAAAUGGACUUUUCCCACCAUUCACUGACUCAUUAGGAGAUAGGCAUCUUCUAAAGAUUUUUUUUAUAUUGUGUAAUGAUUGAUAUAUAGAUAAAAUUAUAUAUUACUUGUAAGGUAUGAUGAAUAACAACACUUAAAAACUCAUCACACCUAAAGACAUGGAAAGCUGCCAAUUACCUAUAUGUAUGUUCUUCCUAUUUUCUUACCUCUUUCCCCAUGUCAUUUUUUAUUGUUCCUUGCCAUUUUUUAAUCACACAUGUAUGUUCUCCAAACAUACUGUUUCAUUUUUUGAAGCUUUCUACAUAUAGUGUCUGAAUGUGAAGUCUUACUCAACUUGCUUUUUUGAGUUUAUGUUUAAAAUUCAUUCUUGCGCUUAUAUGCAUGGAUGGUUUACUUGCUCUAUAGUAUUCUGUGUGAGUAUACCACAAUUUAAGUGUUCAUUUUCCUAUCAGUUGACAUUUGUUUUUAGUUUUUGUUGGUAGAAACAGUACACUCAAAACAUCCUUGACUGUCCCCUGGUACACAUAUGCAAGAGACUUUAUGCGUAAGAGUGGAGUUGUUGGCUUGUCAAGUUUUGCAAAAUAAUGCCAGGUAUUUUCCAAAAUGAUGAUAUUCUCUUGAGUAUUACUUCCCUUUGCAAUGUUUUUAUUGUUAAUGUAGCAUAUAUAAAAAAGUAUCUCAUAAUUUUAA